AUGAGGAAAGAGUUACCUGUGGAUAAAGGAGAAACUGAAAAAUUUACAAGUCAAGACUUUUUAAGCAAAAACAAAAAUAUGACUUUUAGUCACCAAUUCAGUACAGUGAAAAAAAAGUUGAAGAAGAGAUAUCUUGGAAAUAACAUCUGGGUUCUUAGCUGCACUGAGUCAAGCCAACUUACAUCUUUCUUUGUCUUUGGCUGCACUUUUCCUAUCACAUCACACUCCAGCAAUGCCAAGUUGUGCUGGCCUCCUACCUCAUUUCUCCUAUUUUGCCCCUGCCCCGCCGCGGCUUUUUGCGGCUUUCCGCCCCGGCCGCCGCGGCUUUUUGCCUCCGCCGCCGCUGCUUUUUGCGGCUUUUCGCCCCCGCCGCCGCGGCUUUUUGCGCCUUUUCGCGCCCGCCGCCGCCGCUGGUUUUUGCCGCCGAGGCUCUUUGCCCCCGCCGCCGCGGCUUUUUGCAGCUUUUUGCCCCCGCCGCCGUGGCUUUUUGUGUUUUGCCCCCGCUCCCGCUGCUUUUUGCCCCCUCUCAGCGGCUUUUUGUCGCCGCGGCUUUUUACCCCCGUUAGCGCGGCUUUUUGCCGCCCUAGCUUUUUGUCCCCGCCGCCGCGGCUUUUUGCAGCUUUUUGCCCCCGCCGCCGCCGCGGCUUUUUGCCUCCCGCCGCCGCGGUUUUUUUGCCCCCGCCGCCGCGGCUUUUUGCCGCCGCUGCUUUUUGCAGCUUUUUGCCCCCUGCCGCCGCGGCUCUUUCCCCUCGCCGCCUCGGCUUUCUGUGGUUUUUUGCCCCCGCUCCCGCUGCUUUUUGCCCCCGCGGCUUUUUCCCCCCGCCGCCGCGGCUUUUUGCUGCUUUUUGCCCCCGCAGCCGUGCUUUUUGCAGCUUUUUGCCCCAGCCACCGUGCCUUUUUGCCCCCGCCGCCGCGGCUUUUUGUCCCCGCCGCCGCGGUUCUGAGGGCGGGAGCGGCAGACUCGGCUGCCAGCUCUACUGGCGUCCUGGUAAGGGCACCGCCGAGGGGCGCUCCUGGUCCAGCUCUCCCGUCUCCGGGGUUCCUUGCCUAGGCGCCCGCGCCCCGGGCUCCCCGCCUUGGCCACUGUGGCCUGCAUAGAGCGGCGCUGCGCGGGGAGGCUAUGGGAGAGAAGAAGGAGGGCGGGGGCGGGGGUGAUGGGGUGGCGCAGGGGCCGCGGCCAGCCGGACGCUGCAGCAGUGCGGGCAGCUACAGAAGCUCAUCGGCAUCUCCAUCGGCAGCCUGCACGGGCUGCGCACCAAGUGCGCUGUGUCCAACGGCCUCACCCAGCAGGAGAUACGGACCCUGGAGGUGAGGCCACUGAAGGUCUGAGGGAGAACUGACUUGUCAGGAACUCCUGUUAAGGAGAAUUAACAAAGUGUGGUUAUUAAAGGAGAACUGAGUUGGGAGUCAGACCUGGAGGACUGCACCCUUGGUUAAGACAUUAUACCACCUUGAGUCUGGCCUGUUGACUGAAGAUACAACAGAGAAAUGCAUAAUGUCCACUGAAUUUAUUAAAGUUCCAAAAUCGGUCGCGCGCAGUGGCUCACGCCUGUAAUCUCAAUACUUCGGCAGGCCGAGGCGUGUGGAUCACGAGGUCAGGAGUUGGAAACUAGCCUGACCAACAUGGUGAAACCCCGUCUCUACUAAAAAUACGAAAAUUAGCCAGGCAUGGUGGCACGCGGCUGUAAUCCCCGCUACUCAGGAGGCCGAGGCAGGAGAAUUGCUGGAACCUGGGAGGCAGAGGUUGCAGUGAGCGGAGAUGGCACCACCGCAUUCCAGCCUGGGUGAAAGAGUGAGACUCCUCCUCAAAAAAAAAAAAAAAAAAAAAAAAGUUGCAAAGUCAUACUCACCUUUCUGCUCUUGUCAGACAAUUAAGGGGUCAUUGAAUACUUCAGCCCUAAUAAUUUGCUUCCUAACAUACAUAUUGCAGUGCUUAUCUAAUUUUAAAUAUCUUUUUGUUUCAACACCUAAUUUUUUAUUUAGAUCUACCUGUAUGUUUAUUUUGCUCUGUAUUCAUUCUUUGAUUUCAGAACUUCAACCUUUCUGAAGCAUGUUUUCAGAGUUUCUUUUUAGUUUCUUUAGUGGAAUUCUGCUGGUGGUGCUUUGUUUUUUCUCUCUAAAUAUGUUAUUUAGCCAUAGGUUGAUGAAUAUUUUUCUUGGUUGAGAAUUUCAGAAUGGCAUUAUUAUUAUUAACAAAUAAUAUUUUUUAUUUUACCUUUCAUUCUUUCCGAUUUCAAUAUGAUUAAAGGUAAUUUGAUUUUUCUAGUGCUAAUUGAAAUAUUUUUCCCUUCCUGAUUCUUUGCUAUUUCUCUAGGAGAUACGUAGGUGUAGGUUUAUCUCCAUUGUAGCUUGCUUAGCAUGCAUGGAAUUUUUCAAUAUGCGGAUUAGUGUCUUACAAAAGUCUAGAGAACUUUCAGCCAAAAUACCAUCACAUAUUGUCCCUUCCCAGUUCCCUUCUUCUAUGAGAACACUCACUAAACACAUGCUACACUUUCUCACGGUAUCUUCCUUGUCUCUUCAUGAUUCUGUCCACAUUUUGCAUUUUUUUAAAUUUUCUGUGAUGCAUUGUGAAAUAUUUAUUAACUCUCACCAUGGCCAUGUCUAAUCUGAUGAGUUCAUUUUUGAGUUUUUAAUUUAAAAUACUAUAUUUUUAUACAAGCUACUUUACAAAUUUUCUACAUCAAUUUUUUAGUCUCCUAAAAUAUAUUCUUUUUUAAAAAAAAUUUUUUAAAGCAAAUGUGCUUUAUAAUCUAACAGUGAUAUUUCUACUAAUGAACCUUUGUGGAUCUGUUUGUACUCUUUUUCUGCUUUCCUUUCAAACGGUGGUAUACCAUUUCCUUGUGUACUUAGAUGCCUCUGAAUGACAAAUAUUUAUUUUUCUCUGAAAAUUAUUUUUGUGCACUUUUGCGGAUUAGUAAGAAGAAAAUUUGCCAAAGAGAAUUUGAAUUUUUUUGUGAGUCUACUAAACGCACCACCAUUCUGGGACCACAUUAUAUUAAUUCUUGGCCUAAAGGUGUUUGGACAUAUGUUUGGACUGCACAUUUAAACAAUUUUUAAAUUAAUUGCUGUAAAUCAUUAAUGAUUGAAUUUCUUUAAAUCUGUCCAAUCUCAAUCAUUUUUAUUUGCCAUUUCCAGGGAAUGUGAAAUGGGACUAAUUUACCUCUGAUUCUUCUUUAUACUGAGGAUAGAAACUUUGGUCCUAGCUUUAGGGAGGAGCUCCUGUGUGAUGCCCUAUCUUAGGAAAAACUAUGUAUUUCUUUACUGUCCUAUGUGAUGUAUGACAGUAGGAAUCUGCACUCAUUCAUUUUGGUACAUGUCCGUAGGGCAAAAUCAGUUUCGGUGUUUAGGUAUAUUUUGUCUGCUCCCUGCAUUCCCAUGGUUUUGACCUUAUAUUUUACUUUUUUUUGUGAACAUACCAAUGCUUCAAUUUUUUUCCAGUAAUAUAAUCCACUAGACUAUAAGAAAGAGAAAAAUUUUGAUUAAACACAAAUUUCAUGUUUUCCUACUCUAAUUGGCUUUUAUGUAAAAAUACAGGUAAAAUUUAUUUGUGCUUUUUUGCUAUUUCUAUUUUGCUAUUCUCUGUUUGUCUAUGUCUUCUCCACGUUGACACAAUUAGGGAAUUUUGUACACUCUUGUGCCAACUGCUUUGAUAGUAACAAAAUGUAUUUCUCAAACUCCUAGGUAUAAAACUCAAGUAUCCACAAUUUAAGUUCUUUUUCCCUCAUUUCUAUUAUGUUUCCAGUCUCAAUAGAAAUCGAUGCCAAUCCAGAAAUACAAGCAUUAUUCUAAUACUUCUCACACAUUACAGAUAUAGAUUAAAUUUUCUAGAUCUCCUUAAAUACUAUCAUUUUUCACUACUUGUAUCUUAACUGUUAAGUUCAACAUUUUCUAUAAUAUUAAUAUAUUGUGAAAAUUUCCUUACUUUCUUAUUUGUCCCAGGUUCAAUGUUUUGCAGUCUCUACCUCACCCUGUGAAGCAUAAACAUUGUACAUGCUGUACAAAUAAUACAUAGUUCAUGUGCUUAGAGAUUGCACAAUUUUUAUUUGGUUGACAAUAGCUAAUGUUUUCUUCUUCAUUUUCUAUUUCCUGAUUUUUCUUUAUUUAGCAUAUACUACAUUAUCAUAAAAAUAAGAACGUGUUACAAACUAAAGCAAAAGCAACCCUAGGAAUAAAAUACACAAAUGAAAUAUAUAAACAUACAAUUAGAUGUACCACGUACCCUUCUAAUUUAUUUAGACAUUUAAUUUUAGUACAAUUUUAAUUAAAGUGUGUGUAUUAUCUGUCA